AGAUUAGCCAGAAGACUAGAGAGAUCUCUGUCUUCAGUCCCUAUCUGUGCUCUUUUCCAUUCCUGCGUCAAUACUGCUGAAGUAGUCUGAGAAGGAAAUAAAUAAAGACUGCACCCUGUCUCAGGAGAAAAGAAUUGGGAGAAUAUCUAAAUCUCUUCUAUAUAUGAGGUGAAGGGCCAUGCCUGGCAGACUACAUGGGGAAUCAGAGGAUCAAGAGGAGUGAAGAGAGGAUCCCUGGAGGAAUGCCCGUCCUCCCUCCACUGACAGCAGCCACAGUUACUAACAGGGUCUUUCUGAUGAGGAGAAUCUGACAGGACCCAGUUGAGCAAGGACUGGAACUGCUUUUGGGGAAUAGGAAAGACAACUGAAAACAAAAAGCCUACCUGAACCUCUUCCAAAAAAUCACUGAAAGAAAGCAGUAAAAUAUAUGGGAAAAUAUGACAACACACCGAAAUGACACCCUCUCCACUGAAGCUUCAGACUUCCUCUUGAAUUGUUUUGUCAGAUCCCCCAGCUGGCAGCACUGGCUGUCCCUGCCCCUCAGCCUCCUUUUCCUCUUGGCCGUAGGGGCCAACACCACCCUCCUGAUGACCAUCUGGCUGGAGGCCUCUCUGCACCAGCCCCUGUACUACCUGCUCAGCCUCCUCUCCCUGCUGGACAUCGUGCUCUGCCUCACUGUCAUCCCCAAGGUCCUGACCAUCUUCUGGUUUGACCUCAGGCCCAUCAGCUUCCCUGCCUGCUUCCUCCAGAUGUACAUCAUGAAUUGUUUCCUAGCCAUGGAGUCUUGCACAUUCAUGGUCAUGGCCUAUGAUCGUUAUGUAGCCAUCUGCCACCCACUGAGAUAUCCAUCAAUCAUCACUGAUCACUUUGUAGUCAAGGCUGCCAUGUUUAUUUUGACCAGAAAUGUGCUUAUGACUCUGCCCAUCCCCAUCCUUUCAGCACAACUCCGUUAUUGUGGAAGAAAUGUCAUUGAGAACUGCAUCUGUGCCAAUAUGUCUGUUUCCAGACUCUCCUGCGAUGAUGUCACCAUCAAUCACCUUUACCAAUUUGCUGGAGGCUGGACUCUGCUAGGAUCUGACCUCAUCCUUAUCUUCCUCUCCUACACCUUCAUUCUGCGAGCUGUGCUGAGACUCAAGGCAGAGGGUGCCGUGGCAAAGGCCCUAAGCACAUGUGGCUCCCACUUCAUGCUCAUCCUCUUCUUCAGCACCAUCCUUCUGGUUUUUGUCCUCACACAUGUGGCUAAGAAGAAAGUCUCCCCUGAUGUGCCAGUCUUGCUCAAUGUUCUCCACCAUGUCAUUCCUGCAGCCCUUAACCCCAUCAUUUACGGGGUGAGAACCCAAGAAAUUAAGCAGGGAAUGCAGAGGUUGUUGAAGAAAGGGUGCUAACAAGGACCACUGGAUCUCUGAAUAUCUAAAAUAAGAUAAUUUAUUAAUCACUUAAUGAGUGAGUGGGCUGAAAUUCAUAUCUGUGACUUAUAACCUCAAACUGGGUACACUAGAUAUUGUGUGUGCUUUUCAAAAACAUCGGUUUUAAUUUAAGUCUAUCUUCCUUUUCACCCUUUUCUCAGAAAUAUUCUUGGCCCUCUCUCGUUUUAUUCCAUGCUUAUAAUCAUAUUUUGUCCAAAACACUGACAUUCCUUAAAGCAGAUUUUAAAGUGAAAAAUGUAUGUUUCUGAACACACAACUCAAUAUGUCAUGAAUUUUGUAUCAUUAAAAAUACAACUGCGGUUAUUUUGUUGUGUCUGUUAUGUGUAAUGUCCUUUUAUUCUUAUUUUCAGAAAAGGGAAUACAUUGGAGAAAAAAACACAGUAGUUGAAAUUUCAGUCCUCAGUGGUGGAAAGUUGCUACUGGUCUGUAAGUAGGUCUUUUUCUCUCACCCUUCAACCACAUCAUUGCCUUUCUCUAGUUCUCUUUCUCCCCUCACCUCCUCUCUCUCCCUCUCCUUCUCUUUCUCUGGAAGACAAGUAAAUUUUUGUAAUGUGCAUUGCAAGAGGGCAAGGGUUUUGCCUUGAUUCCUCAUGAGUAACAAUUAUCAAUGAGUUUUACUGGAUAUAUGAGAUUCUUGAAUCCUCUUCCCCAAUGUGUCUGUGCUUAGAACAUUUAUCUUUCAGAUCCAAUAUAUCACAGGUUUUGAUAUGCAAACAAAUCUUUAUUAAUGAGUCAAAAGAUUGCUGGUAUUAGAGCAUACAAUCUAGCAAUAAUAUUGACACCUAAAAUACUUUUCCUGAACAUUAUUUUCUCAUUAAUUGGACAGCUUCUAAGCACACAUGGUGUCCUGUGAAUUAUGUUAGCUAUUAAGAAACAAAAAUAAAAAGAAUAUUGUUGUUGAUUUGAGGACCUCAAAGUUUGGGUAGGAAAAAUACAAAUAUGCACUCCAGAACACAUUCUUCUAAACUGUAGAGCAGUGAGGAAUGGGAUAAAAGAUAUGUAUGGGCAGUAAGAUACUUGGUCCUGUAAGGAAACAUUAGAUAAAGAGAAGGUCUGGGCAGUAGGCCUUGCACAGCCACACACCCACAUGCACACACAUACAUACCCACAGCAUAAAAGUUGUGUCCCGCCUGGGAAGAAAUCAAAUAAGAGAAUUCACUGUGUUUCCCAUUAUUCAUCCAAUACCUGAUAAUAGUGAGCGAUUUGUUUUAGAAUAUUCUUCUAAAUACAAGAUUCUGUGCUUCAGUAACAACUUACAAGUAUGUGUUACUUUGUUUUGACCAUACAAGGAAAAUUUCUCAAGUAUCAAAUACCAAGACUGUCCCAAAUGUCCGAAUGUUUUAAAUUUAACUGAAAGCAUCUGAGAUUAAGCCCUGUCCUACUCAAGCAGAAUUCCGCAGAGCUCUCUCCGUUCAUUUCUCUUCUCCAUCUUGCAAAAAAAAUGAUAAAUUAGUAUUUAAUUCCUGGAUAUCCUGGAAUUGAAACCUACUGAUUGAAAAAUAAGCAUGUACCACAUAUAAGAAGCAAUAGUUAAAAGCAUAUAAUCAAUAAUUUAAUUAGAAAUUUCUCAAAAGUGAAAAGCCAUCUGUUAAGAUCCGAGUAGAUACACCUUUUUCUUUAUUACUCAAAGAAGAAGGACUCUCUAAAAUCUCAUUCUCUCAUACAUUUCAACAUAAGAAAAAUGGCUUGACUUGAAAUGUGAAUAACCGUAUACCAUGGAAGAAUCUUACAAUUAUAAAGAUAUAACAUGCUUGUAAGGUAAAUUUAAGCCACCACCUCUUAGGAAAUAUUAAAAAUCUGAAAGUUUUAACAAUAUGCUAUAUUAACAUAUACUUAUCAAAACACCAAAACUUUGAGGACUAGUUAUUUUCAAGAUCACAUCGUUUGUAUGACAAAUCCAGAUGUCUACAGUAAGCUGUUAGAAGAUAACCUUGGGUGCCAGGAAAAGGACAUAUUGAGGGAUUUAGAGUACAUACCUCCCUGAGAUUAAGAAAAUUUUCCAUAAGUCUUGUCUUCCCAAAGAACAUGGUAAAAAGUUCAUAUUUUAAAAGUAUUUGCCUGAAAAAUCUGUUUUGCUUCACUUAUAUGUAAUUUUUAGACAUUUAUAAACAAUGUCAAAACAAUAUCGGCAUAUAUUUAUUUGAAAAACAAGGUGAACAAGUUAACUAUGGUUUUAUCUCACCAAAAUAGGUAAUAUUAGUGAGGAUUUCCUCUAGAACUGUGCUGUGCAAUAUGAACCACAUACUUAAUUUUAAACUUUUUAGUACACAUGUUGAAAAAGUAGAAACAGACAAAAUUAGUUCUAAUAAGAUAUUUUAUUUAGUCCAACAUAUCCAAAAUAUUAUCAUUUCAACACAUAACAAAUACAAGAUAAUCAUUAAUGUGAUAUUGCACAUUCCUUUUCUGUACUAAGUCUUUGAAACACCCUGAGUAUUUUACACUUAACAUACAUUUUAAUUCAGACUACCCAGAUUCCAAGCAUUCAAUAGCCACGUGAGGCUAGUGACUAUGGUAUUAAUCAGUACUACUCUAGAAAUUUUGCUUUGAAAGUCAGAUAUGGAUAGAAAAUAAAGUUAAUUAGAAAAUAUGUAUUCUUCUUGAAAUACAUCUUAUAAUACAGUUAUAUUUAUAUUAUUUUGUUUUGGCUAUAAUUUUUCUUUUUUAUAUGUUUUGCCAAGGAAGUCAGGGUUUUAGAGGAGAGUAAAGUUUUUUUUGUUAAUGCUGCAAUAACAUGAGUGCUAAAUCUUGGAAACCAAGGUGAGAAGAUUUAUUUUUAAAAGAAGUUUUAGUUACUGGGUUUUUAAGACAUAUGGUCCUGAAAUCCCACAGUGACAGACUUGAAGAAGAGUUAAACUUAAGAUCCUAAGGAAGAAUGUAAAUGGGUAUUUACUCAUAACAAGUAAGGAAUAUUAGCAUUAGAGUAAUCGACAGACAUUAAUACGUUAAAGGUUUAUCAGAAGGUAAAUGAUAAACAUUAUUUGUAAUUCAUUAAAUUUUUCUUUACAUCAUUU